GGCGCGGCGUGCGCGGGCACGAGGCGUAGUGGUCUCCCCUAAGGCUGAGGCGGCGGCGGGCGCGCGGCGGCGGCGGGCGUGCGAGGCUGUUGUGCUCCCGGCUCUCGUGUUUCCCCUCCUGAGCGGGUGGAGGAGGCCCAAGCGGUGCUGGGCGCGCUCCCCCUUCCUUUCCCUCCGGCGUCCUCUCCCGGCCCUCUCGCGCUGCACUGUCUCUCCGACGCAAGACUGUCCCGGCCCGGCCCCCUCGGAAAACCACACUGAGAGUUGCAUUAAAAACCAGCAUAGUCUCACUGUCGCCCAGGCUGCAGUGCAGUGGUGCCAUCACGCGUCACUGCAACCUCUGCCUCCCGGAUUCAAGCAAUUCUCCACCUCAGCCUCCCAAGUAGCUGGAAUUACAGAUAUGGCUCGUGGACAGCAGAAAAUUCAGUCUCAGCAGAAAAAUGCCAAAAAGCAAGCUGGACAAAAGAAGAAACAAGGACAUGACCAAAAGGCUGCUGCCAAAGCUGCCUUAAUAUAUACCUGCACUGUCUGUAGGACACAAAUGCCAGACCCUAAGACCUUCAAGCAGCACUUUGAGAGCAAGCAUCCUAAGACUCCACUUCCUCCAGAAUUAGCUGAUGUUCAGGCAUAAGGUUGUUUACAGGUGAAUUCAUGACACCUUUGACUCUUCUACUGUCUCAGACCUUAGGUAACAUACCUGCAGCUGCUUUUCUAACAAACUGUUGAUCAGCAAAAAUAAAGGGGCUACAGAAACACUCAUUUUUAUGCUGUUCCCUCUUGGGCUUCAUGCAAAGACAAUUCUGUGUAAAUGUACAGUUGACUCUGAUUUGGAAAUAUGAAAAUCAGUCCAUCCUUGUUAUAAAAAAUUUUUUUACAAUUGUAAUUAUAUUGAUGUUCAUAUUGUGUAAAAUAACUCAUUUAAUAAAAUAGUACUUUGAUUUACGACAUCACAGGAUAAAUGGUUUUAGAAAUUCUGUUCUAACUUUCCACAUUAUUUGCCUUAUAAAAAUCUAAUGAAUUCAUCAGCUAGAAUUGCAAGUGCAAUUCUUAUAUCCCUUUCUCUGCUCAGUGGCAGGUUCCUCAGUUAAACUAGAGCAGACUGAUUCAUUAAAAUUGUGCAUACGAUUUUAUGGGCAGCUGAUGAUCUAGGUGAAAAAUGACUUAUCUGCUGCCUUAGUAUAUUGCGGUUAUGUGUCAUUGUACCCCUCUGAUCAUUUCCUGUGUUUGAGUUGGAAUAUUUAAAAUUGCAGUAUGACCUGGCUCUAACUGCCAGUCAGGUGUACCCUGUAGAUAACUGAUAGCUUCCUAAAAGCGGUUGGAUUGUCAGUGAGCCCUUGUGAAAGGUUAGGUUCUAAUGUAUAUGCCGUAAUGAAAUAAUCAUUAAGCCUAUUGUUUAAUGCAAAAUAUGGAACAAAUGUGAACUGGUAAAGGUCGAUCUUGAUACUAUAUUCUUUGAAAAUUCUUGAAGUUCUUUAAUUUGAAAUUGAAACAUUAAUUUUUGAGGUUUUUGGAAGUUACUAUUUGGCCAUUUUUACAAAUGGAUUUUGCAUUAACAGGAAGAUUGGAAUGACUUGUGGCUGGAUUAAUUCCCAGAACCCUCUCCCUCCUUUCUUUUCUAAGUGAGUUGUUGAUUUUAGGAGUUUGCUUUGUGCUGUUACCUAAAAUCAGAGACUGGUGUACAGUAUGACUUCCAUCUGAACUUGAAAAGUAUUAAAAUGGGUCAAUAUUCACAUUCUUUUAGAUCUCAGGAUGGGAAAAUGGGUUUGUUCAGAUGGAUAUGGUAAAUCUUACCCAAUUAAGGAAGGCUAAUUUUAGAGUUCUUCUAAUUUGCUUGUGUCAACUCUUAACUUGUAAAACUGCUGUUAACUCGGUUUAAAUUUUUAAAUUAAUAUAAUAGAAAGAACACUAAAAUACUUACUGGUAACUGCUUAGAGCCAUUUAUCUGAUCCUGUGGAUUACAGAAUGCAUUCCCUCUUCUGCUGUAGCUUAUCAUUGCUUUGUUUUGUAGCUCUGCAUAUUUUGCCCACCUUGUCUUCCCUGUAAGUUUAAGACGUUUCCAAGGAAAAGCUUCAGGGCUGAUAGUUUCUUAGCAAUUCCUAUUCUUAUGCCCUUACUUUAAAAUAGUCCUUUUAUUUUGUGUAUUUUAUUUCCUAAGUUUCAGAUGUAAUAUCUGUUGUUUCCUAACAUGUCGAUUACCAGAACGUUAGAAUUUUACCUAAUUUCUUGUGGAUAUUGCAGAAGUUCUGGUUAAAUCACAACUUAAAAGUUUUUAAAAGUGCUUUGAGCAUAUGUAUAUGUUUAGUGACAAAUCAUAUAAAACCAUUCACAAGUUUUGGUUUUUUUUUUUUCGUUUGUUUUAGUGACUAAUUCAGGAUGAAAGUUUUUUUGUUCUUGUAUUUAACCCUUUUUUAUAAGCAGCUGAAGACACCAUAUUUAACACUAUAUCUCAGUGAUAGGGAAAUAGCUGCAUUGAUCUUACAUGAGCAUAAUCAUCCUUAUACUUCAUGAGGGGAUUAUUAGUACAAUCCCCAUUUUACUGUGUUUGAGUUAAAAACCAAACAUCCCUGUAAUUUAAUUUGAAGAUUCUUUAACAGAUUGCAGCAAAGUUCAUUAUAAAACUGUUAUGGUGUCUUCAAAGACUUGAUAAAAUAACACUGAGAGAGAAUUGGUCCAUUUGUAUGCUGUAUUUCUAUUACUUGCCAAAAGGAAUGGGGUUAAGAUUAAACUUGUUUCCAUUCUCUUCACAUGGAUAUUCAUCCCCAUGUUUAACUGACACACUGGGGGCUCAGUUGUGUGCUGUAAUGUCUUAUUAAAGAAGAUAUUAAAGAAAA